AUGGCCCCUAAACGCCAGUCUCCACUCCCACUUCAAAAGAAGAAACCAAGACCACCUCCUGCUCUGGGACUGGAGGAGACAUCGGCCUCUGCAGGCUUGCCGAAGAAGGGAGAAAAAGAACAGCAAGAAGCAAUUGAACACAUUGAUGAAGUACAAAAUGAAAUAGACAGACUUAAUGAACAAGACAGUGAGGAGAUUUUGAAAGUAGAACAGAAAUAUAACAAACUCCGCCAACCAUUUUUUCAGAAGAGGUCAGAAUUGAUCGCCAAAAUCCCAAAUUUUGGGGUAACAACAUUUGUCAACCAUCCACAAGUGUCUUCACUGCUUGGGGAGGAGGACGAAGAGGCACUGCAUUAUUUGACUAAAGUUGAAGUGACAGAAUUUGAAGAUAUUAAAUCAGGUUACAGAAUAGAUUUUUAUUUUGAUGAAAAUCCUUACUUUGAAAAUAAAGUUUUCUCCAAAGAAUUUCAUCUGAAUGAGAGUGGUGAUCCAUCUUCAAAGUCCACCAAAAUCAAAUGGAAAUCUGGAAAGGAUGUGACGAAACGUUCAAGUCAAACGCAGAAUAAAGCCAGCAGGAAGAGGCAGCAUGAGGAACCAGAGAGCUUCUUUACCUGGUUUACUGAUCAUUCUGAUGCAGGUGCUGAUGAGUUAGAAGAGGUCAUCAAAGAUGAUAUUUGGCCAAACCCAUUACAGUAUUACUUGGUUCCUGAUAUGGAUGAUGAAGAAGGAGGAGAAGAUGAUGAUGAUGAUGAUGAUGAUGGUGAUGAAGGGGAGGAAGAAUUAGAAGAUAUUGAUGAAGGGGAUGAGGAUGAAGGUGAAGAAGAUGAAGAUGAUGAUGAAGGGGAGGAAGGAGAGGAGGAUGAAGGAGAAGAUGACUAA